CCUUCAACUCCGCGGGGCAGUAGGAGUUAGUUAGCAAAGAGCCGAGGCCGGGCGCGCGACCCUCGUCCUUCUGCCCCUGGCCGCACACUUUGCGCACAUCUCUUUUUCUGCAUGGUGGAUAUUAUUUUUCAUUAUCCUUUUCUGGGUGCUAUGGGUGAUCAUUCCAAGAAGAAGCCCGGGACGGCCAUGUGCGUGGGCUGCGGGAGUCAGAUCCACGACCAGUUUAUCCUGCGGGUGUCGCCCGACCUCGAGUGGCACGCGGCCUGCCUCAAGUGUGCCGAGUGCAGCCAGUACCUGGACGAGACGUGCACGUGCUUCGUGAGAGACGGGAAGACCUACUGCAAGCGGGACUAUGUCAGGCUGUUCGGCAUCAAGUGCGCCAAGUGCCAGGUGGGCUUCAGCAGCAGCGACCUGGUGAUGAGGGCGCGGGACAGCGUGUACCACAUCGAGUGCUUCCGCUGCUCCGUGUGCAGCCGCCAGCUGCUGCCUGGGGACGAGUUCUCGCUGCGGGAGCACGAGCUGCUCUGCCGCGCCGACCACGGCCUCCUGCUCGAGCGCGCCGCGGCCGGCAGCCCGCGCAGCCCCGGCCCGCUUCCCGGCGCCCGCGGCCUGCAUCUGCCCGACGCUGGGUCGGGCCGGCAGCCCGCGUUGCGCCCGCACGUGCACAAGCAGACGGAGAAGACGACCCGCGUGCGGACUGUGCUGAACGAGAAGCAGCUGCACACUCUGCGGACCUGCUACGCCGCCAACCCGCGGCCCGACGCUCUCAUGAAGGAGCAGCUGGUGGAGAUGACCGGCCUGAGCCCGCGGGUCAUCCGCGUCUGGUUCCAGAACAAGCGCUGCAAGGACAAGAAGAAAUCCAUUCUCAUGAAGCAGCUGCAGCAGCAGCAGCACAGCGACAAGACGAGCCUUCAGGGACUGACUGGGACGCCCCUGGUGGCGGGCAGUCCCAUCCGCCAUGAGAACGCCGUGCAGGGCAGCGCAGUGGAGGUGCAGACGUACCAGCCGCCGUGGAAGGCGCUCAGCGAGUUUGCCCUCCAGAGCGACCUGGACCAACCCGCCUUCCAACAGCUGGUCUCCUUCUCCGAGUCCGGCUCCCUAGGCAACUCCUCCGGCAGCGACGUGACCUCCCUGUCCUCGCAGCUCCCGGACACCCCCAACAGUAUGGUGCCGAGUCCCGUGGAGACGUGAGGGGGACCCCUCCCUGCCAGCCCGCGGACCUCGCAUGCUCCCUGCAUGAGACUCACCCAUGCUCAGGCCAUUCCAGUUCCGAAAGCUCUCUCGCCUUCGUAAUUAUUCUAUUGUUAUUUAUGAGAGAGUACCGAGAGACACGGUCUGGACAGCCCAAGGCGCCAGGAUGCAACCUGCUUUCACCAGACUGCAGACCCCUGCUCCGAGGACUCUUAGUUUUUCAAAACCAGAAUCUGGGACUUACCAGGGUUAGCUCUGCCCUCUCCUCUCCUCUCUACGUGGCCGCCGCUCUGUCUCUCCACGCCCCACCUGUGUCCCCAUCUCGGCCGGCCCGGAGCUCGCCCACGCGGACCCCCGCCCUGCCCCAGCUCAGCGCUCCCUGGCGGCUUCGCCCGGGCUCCUAGCGGGGAAAAGGAAGGGGAUAACUCAGAGGAACAGACACUCAAACUCCCAAAGCGCAUGAUUGCUGGGAAACAGUAGAAACCAGACUUGCCUUGAAAGUGUUUAAGUUAUUCGACGGAGGACAGAGUAUGUGAGCCUUUGCCGAACAAACAAACGUAAGUUAUUGUUAUUUAUUGUGAGAACAGCCAGUUCAUAGUGGGACUUGUAUUUUGAUCUUAAUAAAAAAUAAUAACCCGGG